GUCGUUGGUAAGGGGCUGGCGGCCGGGGAGCUGCGUAGCUCCCGGCCCCGCGGCCAUGCCCAAGCGGAGCUGCCCCUUCGCGGACGUGGCCCCGCUACAGCUCAAGGUCCGCGUGAGCCAGAGGGAGUUGAGCCGCGGCGUGUGCGCCGAGCGCUACUCGCAGGAGGUCUUCGAGAAGACCAAGCGACUCCUGUUCCUCGGGGCCCAGGCCUACCUGGACCACGUGUGGGAUGAAGGCUGUGCCGUCGUUCACCUGCCAGAGUCCCCAAAGCCUGGCCCUACAGGGGCCCCGAGGGCUGCACGUGGGCAGAUGCUGAUUGGACCAGACGGCCGCCUGAUCAGGAGCCUUGGGCAGGCCUCCGAAGCUGACCCAUCUGGGGUAGCGUCCAUUGCCUGUUCCUCAUGCGUGCGAGCCGUGGAUGGGAAGGCGGUCUGCGGUCAGUGUGAGCGAGCCCUGUGCGGGCAGUGUGUGCGCACCUGCUGGGGCUGCGGCUCCGUGGCCUGUACCCUGUGUGGCCUCGUGGAUCUUUUUAGGACGCUGGUCGUGUUGCCUUAGGGCCCCCAUGUCAGUGCCGUCAUCUAGACUGAUGAUGCCCGCAGUGAUCCUGUCUCCAGAUAAGGUCAUGUCCUGAGGUGUUCUGGGUUAGGACUUUGACGUUUGAAUGGUGGGGGGUGGUGGACACAAUUCAGCCCCUGACAGCAGCUUUUCUCUCCCCUCCCUGACGCUGUCGCAGCUGCAGUGACAUGUACGAGAAAGUGCUGUGCACCAGCUGUGCCAUGUUCGAGACCUGAGGCUGGCUCAAGCCGGCUGCCUUCACCGGGAGCCACGCCGUGCAUGGCAGCCUUCCCUGGACGAGCGCUCGGUGUUCACACUGAACUGUGGGGUCGACGGGAGGGGUGCCUUUUACAUGUUCUAUUUUGUAUCCUAAUGACAGAAUGAAUAAACCUCUUUAUAUUUGCA